AGAGGAGACUCGGGGGCCAUUUUGUGAAGAGACGAAGACUGAGCGGUUGUGGCCGCGUUGCCGACCUCCAGCAGCAGUCGGCUUCUCUACGCAGAACCCGGGAGUAGGAGACUCAGAAUCGAAUCUCUUCUCCCUCCCCUUCUUGGUUACAAAACACUUGAAAUAUAUAAGUUAGUGGAACUUUGCUUGAGGUAGGUAUUAACUCUCUUUCUCAGACGGAAACUGAGGCAGAAAAGUGUUGGUUGCUAGGGUCAUAUUAAGUCAGUAGCAGCACUAGUAAGGAAUUUGACCACGAGGUCAGUCGAGUGGUUUUUACCUAGUUAAUGGAAUACCUAGUUAAUAUAGUUCUAAAACUACUGUAUUGCAAUCUUUGCCAAGAACCUGAUGACGGAAACCACGAGGUAACUGGAAAUUCCCAAAUUGCGCUUAAGAAAAAUACUACGAGACUUGAGAAUUUUUUAACGUAACUUCCUAAGUGUAAGAUGACAAAAUUUGACUUUCGGGAUAUUCUGGCGUUAAUUUUCCCGUCCGCCUAAAUGUGGGCAAAAAUUCACAGCUACGUUAUAUUAAGCAAAUAUUAACAGUGCCUAUUAUUUGCUGGGUGCUGAAAUUUGAUAAAAAACUUAAAAGUUAAAAAAAAUUGUUUAGAUCUUUAGUGUCACAUUGACUUAUCUGGGACAUCGCUUUUUUUAAUCCUCACAUGAGAUUUGGCUAAGUUUAUUUUUCACAAUCUGUUAAUCUCACAAAAACUAAAGCUGUUAAGCACAGUUUAAACCCAUUCUGCAGGGUAAGAAAUUCAUCUGUAAGGCAAUCUAUUUGAUAGGAAGUAAAAUAAGGGUCAAAAACAUCGCGACCCCUUUCUUAAGGCUUAAACAUGUAUAUUAUUACAGGAACUUAAAACUAAAGUUUAUCAUUGUGCUGAACUGUUAGAAAUGAGGUUAGGGUAAAAAUGGGAAAUCAUGAAGUAAAAAUGUUGGCAAGGAGAAAUGUCAGAAAUUAGUAUUUAAGAACUGUUAAUAGUAGUUGAAAUUGAUUGACGGGCACUUUUCUUUGAGGUUUUCGAAAAUGGGUUCCUUCCGGUCAGUAUGUAUAUCAGCGCACCAAAAAUUCUUUGAGUUAAUAUCCGAAACUGUUUGCCACGGUAUUUAUAUCACAAUUCUAGGUGUGUUCUCAACUAGAUAGGCGUUUAGUAACAUUUUCAUAUUGGCUAGGGGGAAAAGUUGAAGAAGGAUGGCCAGGUUGCAGGUUUUCUGACCUUUUUUUUCCCCCUCAUGCUAGUGCCACUCUCGGGAAUACUUGGUGGUUGAUGUUCCUUCUGUAGAGAAUUUAAACAGCUUACGUUUGUAAUUAAAUCUCUAGAGGAUUUGACAUGGCAUUCGACCUUGUUUUGGAUGGAAUGGCUGUGCGAAACAAGCAAAGAAUAAACUCCAAAAUAGCUAGUUGCUCUAAUUUUAAAGACUAAGGGGCAAAUUAUUAAAUCUUAAUAAAGUGUUGAAUGUGAGAGGUGUUGGCUGGGGAGUAAGUUUGCCUAGGAGUUAGGAGAAAUAGAUUUUAAUCCUCCUUAGGCAAAUAAGGGGACUUAGACUUUUUUUUAAAACCUAUUUGAAUUUUUAGUUUCUAAUUCAAAUUUUUUGUUGCCAGAAGCCUAAAAACUGUACAGAUUGAGUUUUAUUAAAAGCAGUUUUGUUUUUUUUUUUUUUUUUUUUUUUUUUUUUUUUGAGACGGAGUCUCGCUCUGUCGCCCUAGGCUGGAGUGCAUGUCGUGGCACAAUCUCGGUUCACUGCAACCUCCGCCUCCCGGGUUCAAGCGAUUCUCCUGCCUCGGCUUCCCGAGUAGCUGGGAUUACAGGCGUGUGCCACCGCACCGGGCUAAUUUUUAUAUUUUUAGUAGAGACGGGGUUUCACCGUGUUGGCCAGGCUGGUCUCGAACUCCUGAGCUCAGGGAGUCCUCCUGCCUUGGCCUCCCAAGGUGCUGGUAUUACAGGCGUGAGCCACCGCACCCGGCCCCGGUUUUCUAAAUUGGUAGUUAUUAUUACUAUUCUUAACCACAUUAUUUCAGUCUUCAAGUACUUUAUUAGUAGUUGUCUCUGGGGAGCAUUAUUUGCUCUUAAUAUGCAUAUUCAUGUAUUCUCAUUGGAAAUGGGAAGGUUUUGGUUUUGUGCAUACUAGAUUUACUAGAGGAUUGGUGAGAACCAGAACUUUGAGGUGUAGCAUAACUACAGGUAUUCUCGAUAUUGGAAAUUUUGAGUUUAUUAACAUAAAAGGAAAAAAGGUUUCUUUGGUACAUUUACUAUCAUAGGUUAUGUGUUUUUGGAUUUAUUUAUAUUGUAUCAGGAAAACAUUAUUUGGUGCUCUAACUUGAUUCUGUCACAGUACACUGGAAGGUCAGGCAUUUUGUUUAAAGAAUUGAUUCUAAGGCCGGGUGUGAGCCACGCCGCCUGGCCUCAAGGAAUAUUCUUGAUUGAAAAUGGUGCUAAAGUUGGUCUUUUUAUGAGUGGUAGCUCUUCAGUUUAACAUAAAUAACAUCUUGGGAGAUACUGAGCUUUUUGAUAUUGAAAGAUAGAAUUGGUUUCUUUUCACAUUUUUCUUUAUUUUUAAGCUUAUGUCUUGUGGCACCUGUACAAAGGACUUGGUUGUGGUUGAGCUAUAAAGUUAUGUAUCUUGAAAAUUGAUUACCAGGUUUGGGCUGUGGCUCCAAAUAAGAAAAUGAAAUGUUUCACCAUAACUGUAUUUCAUAAACAGGAAAAGAACAUUCAGAUGUAUAUUUCUUACAAUUCUUCACAAACUUUUUCCGCAAUUUGUACAUUCAUACAGUUUUCACACAUCAAAUGUAAAAAUUAACUGUCAUUCCUACACUGUUCUUUUUAAAAAUGUAUGGUACUUGUUGCUGCUGUAGUCAUUCAUGUAUAGUUGGCUCAAGGAACACUUCUAAAAGCUCAAUUAAAAAUUUUUUUUUUGAGACAGGGUCUCUCUCUGGCCUGGCUGAAGUGCAGUGGCGUGAUCAGAGCUCACUGCAGCCUCGAACUCCUGGGCUCAAGUGAUCCUCGCUCCUCAGACUGCUAAGUAGCUGGGAUUUCAGGCUACCACACCCUGCUAAUGUUUUUUGUUUUUAAUAAAGUCUCGUCAUGUUUCCCAGGCUGGUCUCAAACUACUGAGCUCAAGCCGUGCUCUACCCUGGCCUCCCAAAGUGUUGGGAUUACAGGUGUGAGCCACCACACUUGGCCUUAAAAUAUUUUAAUUUCCUCAAAUUUACAAAGGAGAAUAAGACCUCAUGGCUAAAUUGAACAGUGAGUGCAGCUAGUUCAUUGUUUGCACAAGGAACUACAGUCUAAUUGCAGUUCCUAUUUUAGCUGAUGAAACAACCAGUUUGUCAUGGAAAUUAUUUUAGUGUGGUAUUAUGUACCAGAUUUUUAGAAUCCAUAACUUGAAAUUAGCUUUACACGCUACAUAGUAAAUAGUGGACUACAGAAACAAAAGUAUUAACAUAAGGACCUUAAUUUUUUUCACCUAUUUUAUGACCUUAAAUAUUCAGUAUUUUUUUAAUUCCAUCUGUAUUUUCGUUUUGUCAGUGAGUGGAAUAAUGUGCUCCUUAUUUAAAACAUCUUUUCCCCUAACAGUAGAACCUAUUAGGUCUUGUGGUUUGAUCACUCACUGGUUUUGAGAAUAGAUGAGUCAUCUCUAGUAUAGAUCUUCAUGGUAGGCCAUUCACCUUCAGUCUAUUACUCAUAGCAAAAACUCCACGGACUUUUUUAAGUUUAAAACCCAUGAAUCUGCUUAGGUUUUAUAAUCUCAGUAUUUGACAUUUGCUCACUAUUUCAUCUCUAUUUGUUGGCCCGGUUUUUCUGUAUUUUCUUUGCCCAAACUGCUCAUUAUCAAGAUGAACAUUUGGGAUAUACUCUUUUUGAGACCCUCAAGGGCAUAUUGACAUGAAUUUAGUUAAUUUUAGUCAUCUAUUGAUGUUGAAGAAUUGUGAAGACAGUCACUGGUAGAGGUGAUUCUAUGGAGGCUAUCCCAUCCCAGUGGAAUGUUAAUGCUUUACCAAAAUGUGUUAGCUGCAGUAGACAGAUGUUUCUGUCUUGGGGGUUUAGGGCACAACAUUUCUGAGGAACUCUGACUCAAUCUGUCCCUUCUCCUUUCACAGGGCAGCAAGGCGAACCCCAUCCCUACUCACUGGAGCUCAGCUUUGAUUUUUAACCUCCCUUCCCCACCCUUCCAGAACACACACAUUCCAUUCCAAAACUGAUUUUAUAAAGACAUUUUAAACAUAAUGAUGCAACUUGGUGUGCACUACAGCAAAUGUACAGGUGUUUUUUUUUUAAUUGUUUCCAAAACCGGGACCUGGAUUUAAGAUGUAAUUUUUAAAAUUUCUAUUUCUAUUUUUUCUGCAGCAGUUGGGUUAGAGGAGGAGGAGCCUUUUAGCCUCUCAUAAACUGACCUCUCUACUUCCUCGUGUAUUUUUAAGAUUGAUUGAUGAUGUGGAAAGGGCUUUGCUUGUCUGCUACUGAAAACUUUAUCCUUGCGGUUUUUGUGGAAACUGCUUUUGGAAAGAGAAAAGAAAUGAACUUUACUGACUUGACAUUUUUGCACCUCCCGUUUUUCUAAUCUGGGCUAUUUUUAUUUUUGUUUUUUUACAGUGAGAUUUUUUUGAUCUUCAGCUACAGUAAGUUAUUCCAAUUUUUUUUUAACAUUUUUCCUGACUUUCCGCUGAUUUCCUUUUUAUUGUUGUUACUAGUUACUAUUACUUAUUAUUAUUAUAUUAAUACUUAUGAUGGUGAUGAUGAUGAUGAUAAUGACACUGAUGAUUUUUAACCGGAUUAAAAUCGAGUUUUUCUGAAUGUUUCUAAGAAUUUCUCCGGCCUCCUGAUUGACUUUGGAGUUUUGCAUCUUGGGAGAGAAAGCGAAGGCAUUAGUAUUUUUAAGUGGUUUGAUCACGUAAACCUUUUCUCUCCCAACCCCACCCUUGCCCUCAUCCCCUUCCCCACACUGAAAAGAAUUUUACUGGCUGUUAAGUCUAUGACCUUAUUUUUCCUGAUCUUUAACUUAACUGUUUUAGAGCAUCUCUGGACGUCUGUAUUUUUAAUUUUUUUUAUUUUUGUUUUUUUAUUUUUAAUCUUUCAUUUGUUAAAUUUUUAAACUGUGCUGCAAUAAAAUGUGUGUGGUACUACUUAACACUUAUGAUCGUGAUGGCAUUUUCCCUGAAAGCCAUCUUCCUCCUGUUUCCCUUGAAAUCCCAUCCUGCUUUUCCUGUACACUACCCCUCACAAACCACAAGCUGCAGCAACAUGGAUGCCCAGCCUGGAGCAGCAGCAGCCAGGAUGACCUGGAGCCAGGGGGGCCUUCGGAACAGAUGCACACCCUUCCUGGGUGAUGUUUUCGGCUUUGUGAGAAACCUUACCAUCAAACACGAUGGCCAGCAACGUUACCAACAAGACAGAUCCUCGCUCCAUGAACUCCCGUGUAUUCAUUGGGAAUCUCAACACUCUUGUGGUCAAGAAAUCUGAUGUGGAGGCAAUCUUUUCGAAGUAUGGCAAAAUUGUGGGCUGCUCUGUUCAUAAGGGCUUUGCCUUCGUUCAGUAUGUUAAUGAGAGAAAUGCCCGGGCUGCUGUAGCAGGAGAGGAUGGCAGAAUGAUUGCUGGCCAGGUUUUAGAUAUUAACCUGGCUGCAGAGCCAAAAGUGAACCGAGGAAAAGCAGGUGUGAAACGAUCUGCAGCGGAGAUGUACGGGUCAGUAACAGAACACCCUUCUCCGUCCCCUCUACUCAGCUCCUCUUUUGACUUGGACUAUGACUUUCAACGGGACUAUUAUGAUAGGAUGUACAGUUACCCAGCACGUGUACCUCCUCCUCCUCCUAUUGCUCGGGCUGUAGUGCCCUCGAAACGUCAGCGUGUAUCAGGAAACACUUCACGAAGGGGCAAAAGUGGCUUCAAUUCUAAGAGUGGACAGCGGGGAUCUUCCAAGUCUGGAAAGUUGAAAGGAGAUGACCUUCAGGCCAUUAAGAAGGAGCUGACCCAGAUAAAACAAAAAGUGGAUUCUCUCCUGGAAAACCUGGAAAAAAUUGAAAAGGAACAGAGCAAACAAGCAGUAGAGAUGAAGAAUGAUAAGUCAGAAGAGGAGCAGAGCAGCAGCUCCGUGAAGAAAGAUGAGACUAAUGUGAAGAUGGAGUCUGAGGGGGGUGCAGAUGACUCUGCUGAGGAGGGGGACCUACUGGAUGAUGAUGAUAAUGAAGAUCGGGGGGAUGACCAGCUGGAGUUGAUCAAGGAUGAUGAAAAAGAGGCUGAGGAAGGAGAGGAUGACAGAGACAGCGCCAAUGGCGAGGAUGACUCUUAAGCACAUAGUGGGGUUUAGAAAUCUUAUCCCAUUAUUUCUUUACCUAGGCGCUUGUCUAAGAUCAAAUUUUUCACCAGAUCCUCUCCCCUAGUAUCUUCAGCACAUGCUCACUGUUCUCCCCAUCCUUGUCCUUCCCAUGUUCAUUAAUUCAUAUUGCCCCGCGCCUAGUCCCAUUUUCACUUCCUUUGACGCUCCUAGUAGUUUUGUUAAGUCUUACCCUGUAAUUUUUGCUUUUAAUUUUGAUACCUCUUUAUGACUUAACAAUAAAAAGGAUGUAUGGUUUUUAUCAACUGUCUCCAAAAUAAUCUCUUGUUAUGCAGGGAGUACAGUUCUUUUCAUUCAUACAUAAGUUCAGUAGUUGCUUCCCUAACUGCAAAGGCAAUCUCAUUUAGUUGAGUAGCUCUUGAAAGCAGCUUUGAGUUAGAAGUAUGUGUGUUACACCCUCACAUUAGUGUGCUGUGUGGGGCAGUUCAACACAAAUGUAACAAUGUAUUUUUGUGAAUGAGAGUUGGCAUGUCAAAUGCAUCCUCUAGAAAAAUAAUUAGUGUUAUAGUCUUAAGAUUUGUUUUCUAAAGUUGAUACUGUGGGUUAUUUUUGUGAACAGCCUGAUGUUUGGGACCUUUUUUCCUCAAAAUAAACAAGUCCUUAUUAAACCAGGAAUUUGGAGAAAAAAAAAACCCUGGUUUUUUAUUUUUGUAUUUUAUUAUUGUUUACUUCAAACUUUGUUUUACAGCGUCCUCCACAAAACCUCUAGAAUGCACUAGAUAUAUUUUUCUUGGAGUCAUAAUCAUGAUGCAUACCAACACAACACUACUCAAAUUAUAUUUCAUUGAGAUGCAUGUUGCAUUGAGGAGUCAACUUGACAUAGAGUGGAGACUUUUUCAAAAUGGCUUUUACAUCCUAAUGAAAGUUUGGGAAGUAUAUCCUCUCUGCCUUUUCAUCAGUGCUUUGUGGUCCAGCUGGCACCCUUUCUGAGGUUUGUGUUUUGUGCUAAAUGGUUUUGUCCUUAAAUAGGAGAGGCUCAAAAACAUCAAGAUUUCAGGAAAAUGGCGACAGCUGCAUAAUGGAACCCCCCUGCUUCUAUUUUGUUCUUUUAAUUACUAUUUAUAGCCCCAGUUACCUUCUGAAUUCUGAAGUGUAUAUACCUCCAUGUUCCUGAAAACAAGAAAACUCUUACUUCCUGAUAUUCCAUAGACUGCCUUCCCAGGUGAUUGAGAACAUAGAGAAUGUUACACAUUUAUUUUACUCUAAAUGAUCUUUUACCCCUGUUAGCUAAUCUUUGUGUUUUCCUCAACUUUAUUAAUUACAGUGAUUGCAUUUUUAGCAUCCAGUUGUAAGAUGAAUAUAUUAAACAGCUACCAGUGUUGGUGAUACCUCAUCCUUGAAAGGCUUAGUUCAUUUGUGUUUUAUACUUCAGUUUUUCCAGCAUAGCAGAAAAUGCCGCUUAUAAUUUUUGUGCACACAAACCUUGGAUUCCCCUGUAAAGUUGCUAUUGUUUCAUAGCAUGCGGCACUGGCCUUUUUUCAUCCUACUCAUUACAGGCAAAACUCAUGUCUUAUUUAUGAGGAUUUUAUAGAUCAUUUUCUGUAACAGGUGACAAAAGCAGAAAAGAAUGAAGAGGCUGAAGUAUGAACUACCCUUGGAGCCCAUAUACAUGAUAUAGGCAAUUUCUUUUGUAUGUUAAUUCAGUCAAAAAUACUACCCACUUGAUGUUUUCUAAUCUGAUGUGAGCUCAUGUUACACAGACUUUUAGUAAGUAACCCGUGACUAGAAAAUAAACUGGAUGCUUAGGAGAGAGUGUCAGAUGUAUAAGAUGCUAAUAAAACCUGUUUAAUAUUAUUGUUAGCUGUAAGUUUUUGGGAAAUACUGAACAAAUUAGUCCACAAUCAAGUGUCUACUUUUCCCUUCACUGUAGGGCCUCUCCCUGCACAGAGCAGUCUGUUUAGCUGUGAACACCACAAUCUGCAGAUGUUCAAGUCCCUUACAUAAAAUGGCAUAGUAUUUAUAUGUAACCUAUGCAUAUUCUCCUGUAUAUUUUAAAUCAUCUCUACAUUAAAAUACCUGAUAAAAUGUAAA